GGAAAACUUGGUGAUGUUGAAGUUCAGUUUGGUUAUGUGGCUCCUAGCAGGAGUGGCUCCAUUCUUGUUUGGUCUGGUCUGUUAAGACUCAGCCCAAAACAAACCAGAGUGACUGCAUUGUGGUUUGGCGUGGGCUAUUAAGUCUCAGUCCAAAACAAUGGCAUUCCAUAGUUUUGUGUAACCAUAAUAUAAGAGAUUUUUGGAGUGGUUGAAGGUUGGUCAAGGAAUAUUAAUGAGGAGUUGAAUUGGAACUGUCAUUCUCAUUUUUUUGUCCUCUCUCUACCUUACUCUAUGAUUUUCAGAAAAUGAAUCUUUCUGUACUGUAGUUUUCUCGUAAAUAAAUGGAAGGCAGAUCGAAUUAAUUUCUAAAGUCUCUUUGAAGCCCAAAUGUUCUGAUUAUACUAAACUAGCUUGAAAAAUGUGGUUAUUUUGAAAGUAGCUAUUAAUUUUAGCUAAUUUUGUUAAACAUGUAAAUUUCACAAGAAGCCAGUUCUUAAUUCAUUUCUUUAAACUACUGGUUUACUGGUUGUCAGGCACUCUAUUAGGUAAGGAAUGCACUUAAAAAAAAAGUCCUUAUCUUCAGGCAUGUUAAGCUUUUAAAAACUCUAAAAAACCCUAAAACAUUACCUGUUCAUUGGAGAAUAAUUUUAAAUAUGCUUGGGCAUUUUUGUGUGCUGUUUAUUAAAAAUAUAUGUUACAAAUUUUAAUGUCUUAUUUUUACUAUGUAAAUGUGAGUUUGGCAUAUAAUACACCAUAAUUUGUGAAUUUUCUUAUUGAAUAUCAGGGGAUAUAAUUUUUGCCAUUAUAAACCUUAAAAAACAACACUGUGAUUCCAUCUAUGUAAAUAAAUCUGUUAAAUUCUCUUUUUUCUCUUGGUUCUGUAAACUUGUUAUUCCUAAACAUUAGUUCAUGUAAGGCUGAUCAGGCUUGUAAAUGAAUUUGAUUUGUUUUUGAAAUGUAAUAAUUUUCAAGAUUUGGUCAGUUACAUUUCCUUAUAAUUAGAGAAACUUCUUUGAGAAAAUGAGCUAAAAUUAUACAUUUUUGGGGUGAGAAUUAAACUCUGAAUUAGUAAACAUCCUGAGUGACAUGACUGUACCAACUAAGCAACUAAAGAAAUUGCACUUUUAGUUAAGAUCAAGUGGCUUUUUGAUCAGUGCUCCUGCUCUAAGGAUGAGGGAGGUAAUCCUACCUUAAUGUAGAUCUGAGCUUUUAUUUAAAGACUUUGAUAAUAUCAACAUUUAAGAUAGGUUCUUGAUUGCUUCAGGUGGAGAACCUCUAAAACAUAAUGGCUUCUAUGCUUCAGUUACACAGUUAGCCCUCUUUAAGUUUGUAGAGUAAAAUUAGAACUGAACCUUGAUUUUUCAGCAGAUACAUUCUUGAGAAGGUUAUGAAAAUAGAUUUUGAUAUGUGGAAUUCAUAUUUACUUUAUAAAGCAAAAGAUGUAAAAAUGUUCCAGUGGAAAUAAACCCAACUUCCUGAUAUGUAAGCAUUGUAACUUUUUACUGGCAACUUAAUUACGCUACUGAGAGUUAUACAUGGUUUUGCUAUAUUUCAGGAAAGCCAUACUUCAUCCUUAACUCAUCUCCAAAUUAAAAGCUUGCAUAGCAUAGCAAAAGGGCAUGAACAUCUCAUCAUCUGCUGAUUUAAUUUGCCCUUCAGUUGGUCAAAGGUGAUGAGUGGGCUCCAGGACCAACAUUAGGAUCAAGAGGAUGCCUUUGGCAAAGUCAUUUGUAAGGCUGCCCCGUUAAUGUAUUCUUUUCUCAAUGGGCUUAUUGCUUAAUUGAGGGUACUAUGGAUAUCUGAAAAGUUGAUUGUUGACUCCAGUAUUAAUACAUUGAUUUUUUUUCCCUUAGCUAACUUGAAAAAGUAACAUAACCCAAAAUUCAAUAUUUGGAUAAGUAUGAGUCCGUAUAAUGAAUGUUAGACAAUGAAAACAUGCUCCUGAAACUUCACACUUCCAAAAUAGAACGAAGUAUGGCCAUUGAAGACUGUCUUUCAAAUUUAUCUCUAUAUUAAUAGCAAACUAAAAUUAGUUGUGCAGAUUAGUUGAAGUUUCCCUAGGUCUGACUGAAAUGAGGCUAGACCGCAAGGGUCAGAAAGCAUUAUUUAUUUAUUUAUUUAUUUAUUUAUUUAUUUAUUUAUUUAAGAUGGGGUCUCGCUCUGUUGCCAGGCUGGAGUGCAGUGGCGUGAUCUUGGUUCACUGCAAGCUUCGCCUCCCAGGUUCAAGCGAUUCUCCUGCCUCAGCCUCCCUAGUAGCUGGGACUACAGGUGUGCAUCACCACACCCAGCUAAUUUUUGUAUUUUUAGUAUAGAGACGGAGUUUCACCAUGUUGGCCAGGAUGGUCUACAUCUCUUGACCUCGUGAUGUGCCCGCCUUGGCCUCCCAAAGUGCUGGGAUUACAGGUGUGAGCCACUGUGCCCGGCCAGAAAGCAUGAUUUUUAAUCAAACAUAGGUUUGCAUACUGAUCUUUGAGCUAUAAUCUUUUAAGUGUAGAUAUUUCUUACUGUUAACACAUAUCAUUGCUAACAAAAUGGUAACCUUCUGUAGAAAUCUCCAAAUUUUCAUAUCAGUCAGUAGUUAAUAAACAUUGUCAGGUGCUGUGCUGAGUAUCAGGGCACAAAUGAAUAAGACCCAACUUAUCAUGAUACAGGAAAGGAACCACUGCCAUAAUUACUAUUACAGUAUGCUAAUUACAGUACCUGUUUUUGCUGUUGGAAAUACUUUUGGAUUUUUUUCAAGGCUGAUAAAUAUCCCUAGGGUGUUCUAGCUACUCAUCCUCUUUUUGUUAAUUGUGUACUAUAGGCCAGUGAUGAACUGGACUCUGGAGAUUUAAAAAAAAAAAAAAAGACAUCGGCAUCAGCAAUCAACUUGUUCCUGUUUUAUGACCUAUACAUAUACAGGGAGCUGUCUGAACUCCACUCAACAGUUUCACCAUGAGAUUAUUGUUGACUCCUGAGACCAUUUUAAAAAUGAUAUUUUUAACAUAUAAAAGAAGAAAACAUUAGUGACCCAUAACUGCACAGAUAGAAAAGAAAAAAGUAAUAUGUAAAUGGUAGGAAAAGUCAGAUAAAUCCCAAUUGAUAGAAAGUAAAAGCAUGCUCCCUCUCCCCUCAAGAUAGCUCCCUUUAGUAGUUUCUUUUUUUGGGGGGAGGGAGAGCAUCAUGAUAAAUACCUAAUGCAUGCGGGGCUUAAUACCUAGGUGAUGGGUUGAUAGGUGCAGCAAACCACCAUGGCACAGGUUUACCUAUGUAAGAAACCUGCAUGUCCUUCACAUGUAUCCCGGAACUUAAAAUAAAAUUUAACAAAAAAAAGUAAAAAAUAGUUUCUUUUAUAUCCUUUUAGAAAAAUUCAUUGCUACAUUUCAAGAUAAUGUAGGCAGUGCUUUGGUCCCUUAACAUAUUUGUCACUUAAUGACAGGAAUACAUUCUGAGAAAUGAGGCAAUUUCUUUAUUGUGUAAACAUCGUAGAGUGUACUUACACAAACCUAGAUGGUAUAGCCGACUAACAACUACACGCCUAGGCUAUAUGGUAUUUGCUCCUAAGCUACAAACCUGUACAGAAUGUUAUUGUACUAAAUACUGUAAACAAUUUGUAACACAGUGUUACUGUGUACCUAAAUAUAUCUAUAGAAAAGAUAUAGUAAGAAUGAGGUAUAAUCUUAAGGGUGCAGCAUUUACAGGAACAUUAUUAUGCAGUGCAUGACUAUCAAAUAUUUUUAUCCCUUGAGAGUAAAAUAUGAUAAAGACUUGAUUAAAUAUAUGUUGUUAGUCUGAUUUUUAAAAUAAAUUAAAAUGUUAGCACCUGUACUAUAGCUUUGUUUUAGUAGAAGCUGGUUAUAUAGUGUAGUAAAUUUGCUAUUCAUAACCUUGGGCAAGAUCCAAAAUAGAGCCAUAUUGUAUUAAGUACUUCAUUUUGAUAAACUUCUUUUAUUUCAGUUUCAUAGAUACCUGUUUCAUAAAUUGUCAAUUAUAUCAUUAAUUUUUUUUCCAUUUUUAUUGUCUGGUUUGUUAAUUACAAGGGAUUGAUUCAUUAAAUUCUGUUUAUAUUUCAUCUAAAAAUUUAAAAAGUAAAUUAUAGCAACAAAAUGCUUGGAAAACAUUACAUUCUAUUUGUUUUAUAAGUAAAGUCCAUGAUUAACCUUAAUUUGAAUACUUAAGCUUCAUUUGUUUUACCUAAUCUUCUAAUUGAUUUGCUUAAAGAAAGUAAGUUACUGUCUGUCUUGGAUAAACCAUUUCUUCUCUUCACUUUUGUACUAUGAUUGUAAUGAGAUCAUGUUGCAUGCAUGGCUCAUUUCUUUGUUGGAAUUUUUUAAAGACAUGAUAAUACUAACCGAUGAUAUAUAAACUGGAUUGAUUUUUAAGAGGAAAAAUUUUUCUCCCUCCAAAAGAAAAGAGAUAAUAGUAAUUUAGUUGUUUAGCAUGUUGGAAAUCAGAAAUACUUUGAGUUCCCUUUAUCUUCAUGCAUAUGCAUUCUUAAGAUGUUUUUUAUAUAUAUAUUUAUAUCAUCAGUUUCUUUUUAUCAUUUUUUCAGGGUCUUUUACCUUUCAAGUAACUCAAUUUACUUGAAUUGUUAUUUCAGUAAAUCAUAUUAGGAUGUCAAAAAGCUUACAGAGUUAGUAACAAAAACACAUUGAAGAAAUAAUUAGAUUAUUAAAAACAGUUUCUUCUAUAAUAUAAACUUUGAGGGUCAAGAUGCAGACUUCAGUAUAAUAGGAAGGGGUGACUGAUAGAAUGGUUUUUUUGUUGUUGUUAGAGAAAUACGUAAUAAUGCACUCCAUAAAUAAUUACAUGGGCUUAGUUAAGACGUAGAUUUUAUAUUAAGUGCACAGUUCUUUUAGUAAUAACAUAAUUCAUAUUUUCCUUCUCUUGGUGAAUAAAGAUUCUUUAAAUUUUAUGUUAUUUGUAUUAUUUUCAUCUUCAUUACUGAGCUUUGUGAAUUUAUUUACUUUUUAGUUAAGGUAUGACUCUUACCAGAAAACACUUGUAGAGUAUCUCUUCAGAUAGACUAUUCCAGGAAACAGAGGAAGAUUUACUGUGUUACGUGACAUGUUGUGAGUGAUGAAUAAGCUCAGAGACAAAGGCAAGUGAAGGAGAGAUAACAAACUUGAAGAAUUGCAGAGGUUGUAUUCCAGUCAAGUGUGGUAGCACUGGAUUAUCUAAAUUUAACAGUAUUUGUCCAGGCCAAAGAAUUUUGAACUAUUUUCAGCUGCACUACAGUAAACUUUUAUUAGGAGCAUGUUUGGCCAUUAAGUGACAUAUUUUGGCAACUUUUCAUAGUAUCCGGAUCUCAUCUAAGUAGCAUGUGUUUGGGAUUGUUGUAGAUGCCUGCUAUCCUUACUCAAUUUUGAGAGUGGAAUCUGCCAUUUCCAAGAAGAGGUUUUGACUGGAUCAUCUCGUCAAAGUUAUUCACCUGGCUAUCAGGAUUUCAGUAAGUGGGAAUCAAUGUUGAAAAUAAAAGAAGGACUUCUAAGGCAGAAAGAAAUUGUAAUCGAUCGGCAGAAGCAACAAAUUACCCACCUGCAUGAGAGGAUAAGGGAUAAUGAAUUACGGGCUCAACAUGCCAUGUUAGGACAUUAUGUAAAUUGUGAGGAUUCUUAUGUGGCUAGUUUGCAGCCACAAUAUGAGAACACUUCACUCCAGACACCAUUUUCAGAGGAAUCAGUUUCCCAUUCCCAACAAGGGGAAUUUGAGCAAAAGCUUGCAUCUACUGAGAAAGAAGUUUUACAGCUUAAUGAGUUUCUCAAACAAAGACUAAGCCUAUUUAGUGAAGAGAAGAAGAAACUAGAGGAAAAACUUAAAACUAGAGAUCGAUACAUCAGUAGUCUGAAAAAGAAAUGCCAGAAGGAAUCUGAACAAAACAAAGAAAAGCAGAGAAGAAUUGAGACCUUGGAAAAGUAUCUGGCUGAUCUUCCAACUCUAGAUGAUGUACAGAGUCAGAGUCUACAGCUGCAGAUUCUGGAAGAAAAAAAUAAGAAUUUACAAGAGGCUUUGAUAGAUACAGAAAAAAAACUUGAAGAGAUCAAAAAGCAGUGUCAAGAUAAAGAGACACAGUUAAUAUGCCAGAAAAAGAAAGAAAAGGAGUUAGUAACUACCGUUCAGAGUUUGCAACAAAAAGUAGAAAGAUGCCUUGAAGAUGGAAUCCGCCUUCCCAUGUUAGAUGCAAAACAGCUUCAGAAUGAAAAUGAUAAUCUCAGACAACAAAAUGAGACUGCUAGUAAGAUAAUAGACAGCCAACAAGAUGAGAUUGACAGAAUGAUUUUAGAAAUUCAGUCUAUGCAAGGAAAGCUUUCUAAAGAGAAACUGACCACUCAAAAGAUGAUGGAAGAGCUGGAAAAGAAAGAAAGAAAUGUACAGAGAUUAACAAAAGCAUUGCUUGAAAACCAAAGACAAACAGAUGAGACAUGCUCUUUAUUGGAUCAGGGCCAGGAACCUGACCAAUCUAGGCAGCAGACAGUUCUUUCCAAACGGCCACUAUUUGAUUUGACUGUGAUUGAUCAGCUGUUCAAGGAAAUGUCCUGUUGUUUGUUUGACUUGAAAGCAUUGUGUAGUAUUCUUAAUCAGCGUGCUCAGGGCAAGGAGCCUAAUCUUUCAUUAUUACUGGGAAUAAGAUCAAUGAACUGUUCAGCUGAAGAGACUGAGAAUGACCACAGCACAGAAACACUCACUAAAAAGCUGUCAGAUGUGUGCCAGUUACGAAGAGACAUUGAUGAAUUAAGGACUACAAUAUCAGACCGCUAUGCUCAGGACAUGGGAGACAACUGCAUUACUCAGUGAUCAAGUGUUAGUCCCACAGCAAUAAUGACCUGUUGUUUAAAUGCUGCUGUGUUAUGGAGCCAUAAUGGAAGGUUGCAAGUGACAUGACUUGCACUUAGGGAUUUUUUUUCUGUGGAUUUGUUUUGUUGAAGGGGAGAAGGGAAGUGAAGAGAUUUUGAAGGGGCUUAUCUAAUCAGGCAAAAAGAAAAAAAAUCAAAUUACCUUUGGAAAAUAUGAUAAAAUCUACAAGGAAAAAAAUGUCUAUAUUCUCAAACUACUGAUUGUAGGACCAAGCUGUGAAGAGUACCCUUCACAUGAAGGAGUAGGAUUCCUUUUAAUCCUAUAGCUUUGUGUGUUUGUGUGUGCAUGUAUGUGUGUUGUUGUGUGUGUGUGCACGUGCUUUAUUCACAAAUUUAUAAGGGUUUCUAGGGUCAGAGCAGAGCUUCUGAGAAAGGCACACGCUGUUUAUUCUUAUAUUUCUUUCAUAUAGAAGCUUGUGUUGUACUUUGGGAUUUUCAGUGGCUGGCUGAACAAGAGUUCAAACAGCAGGCAAGUGUUGUCAUGGUAGUACAGGAGGCAAAACCAUUUAUAUUUUGAACACUUACUGCACUGAUAGGAUGUUUGUGGUUGAGCUGAUUUUAGUACUGUAGAUAGGUCAGCUGUUUUUCCAGAGUGAUUGUGGAUUUCCCAAGAGGUGUGAAAUUUUGACGUGAUGCUCUUUUUCCUUAGCAUUGUAAUGUAUGUGUUACAAGAAAGGUUAACAUAACUUGAACUAAUUUUAACAUGUUCCUUACUAUUUACAAUUUUUUAUUUAUAUGUUUUAUAUAUAUACAUAUAUAAAUGUAAACAAAGCCAUAUAUAAUUAAUAAAGGCAUUGGAUCAUUAUUAUAAAAGGAAGAUUAACAAAGUUACCCUGGAACAAUAGCUUACUUAUCCAAAUCUCAACAUUUACAUUUUAACAGUUUUGUAUGUUUCAAAGUUGAAACUACUGUAAGAGAAAGCCAAUACUAUUUAUAUCUGAAUCAACAGUAGCAUAAACAUUUUUUAAUUGAGAUUGUAUUUUAAUCCCUUUUGUUAAAGUACAUUAACAACAGUUUUUCACAGGAUAUGAACUUGGCGAAAUUAGUUCUUAAUCUGAAUUACAGGGUAUUACUAUGAAAUGCAGUUGAUUUUGCAGUAGACGUACAGUCAUUUAAACUUCCAAAUGAGUGUUGUCCAUGUUUCUGUUGGUAUUUUGGAAGGAUUAUACAUUUUAUUGCCUUCAGCAUUGAUUAUGUUCUUUUGAAUAUACUUAGUUUUGGCGAAAGCCUUGUCCUUUGUAAGUUGGUUUGAUCUUGUGAUGCAACCAAGUCUCAUUUAGGUCAAGACUAAAUAAGAGAUGGAGGGGUAGAGGGUGUGACUCAAGCAGGAUAAUAUUGAUUUGAUAAAGAGCAUAUCACAUGCCUGUUUUCUUGCCAGAUAAAGGGCAUAGCACAUGCCUGUUUUCUUAUAUACUAGAAUAAAGGCUCUCCUAGGAAAGAUUUUUCUUAAAUAUUUAAAAGUGAAAAUGUGAGACAAGGCCUUCAAGGAGACUACCCAGGAAGAUACACAGUUUAAAAUGUUGGCUAUACAGCUCUCAAUAGAUUAUUUUAUAGUUAUAGUUGAAUAAUCAGUUAUAAUACACUGUAAAGAAAUCAGAUUUUCCUUCUGUUUGGUGUCUGAGUCCUUCCUGCUCUUCUUACUUCUGAGAAUCUGGGCACUAAGAAAUCAGUAAGUACAUUGUAGUGCUCCUGCAUCCCAGAGUCCUUAACCUAAGGAGGGUCUUAGUCACUGGUAAGAACUUGGCUUUCUAAUUAUAUUCACUUGGUUUUUAACAUUAGUAGCUUGACGAUAAUCAGGGUAUAGUAAAUUUCCACCAAAAAUGUGAUGCGAAGAAUUCUGCCUUGGUCCUUUAUGGUAAAACAGAUAAUAACGUCUAAAAUAGAUCAGCCACAAGUGCAGCAAAUAUUUUUACACUCUCUUUGAAUAGAAUCCCAACCACCCUCCCCCAUGAUUUUAGAAAUAAAGGCUUCCUAAAAUAAUAGAACAAAUUGGCAAACAAUCACUAAUUGGACCAGUAGGUUCUUACUUAAAUAUCUCUCCUAGAUUUUUAGUGUAUGUUUUGGGAUUUUAUGGGUUUAUUUAUUUUUUUUUUUUUAAGCAGACGUUACAGUUUGUUUUAAUCUACUAUAGAUACGUUUUUGUUUUUUGGCUUAGUUGGGGAUAAAAUAAUUUAUUUGUAAGUUAGCUUUCUAAAACUUAGAGAAAGUAAUUUAAUUCACGUAUCUUAAAAAUAAAAUUCCAAAGUUAAAAAAUUUCUGACUUAGUAGGAAGUUAACAAAACUACUGCUGAUGCAUUUCAGUUUCCAAAAUCUGUACCCUCCCCCCAUAAAAAAGGGAGUUAAGAUGUGCUAGUUUAAGUAGUUAGCUGAAUUAUAGAUUGAUCCUCUUAAAAUCUGGAGUUUGUAAAGGGGCCUACAUAAACAGUAGAUAGACUUGGAGGGAUUUUGUGGGGGAAUUGAAACUAAUAGUAUUCUAUCUAGUUUGUCAGUAUUUACUUUUUGAUUUUUAUUUUUCAGAAAAUUUUCCUUUCCCAGGACACCCUCUUGUAUUAGAAUAUCCUCUUCUGUAUCACAUUAAAAACAGAUUUUACUGUUAGACCAAAUAAGAUGGGCAAAUAGCAACACUAGAGCAUCUCACCCAGUUUGAACUAGGAUGUUCGUGGAAGUUAUGACACCAAUAUAUUCCUGAAAUGAAAAUUAACCUAAAUUUUAAAGUGAAUCUAUUUGAAAAUUUACUUAGAUAAUGAAACCUCGUUUUAAUUGUGCUUUUUGUGAAUCCAACACUUGUUUGCUUAGAAAGUAUCUUAUCCAGUAUUAAUAUUUUGUUCUUUUGGGUUUUAAAGUUGAGCUUAUUCAGCCUCAAUCACAUUACAGCAAGCAUAAAGUAACAGUUGACUCAAUGAAAGACCCAAAUUGCCUGUACAGAUAAAAUUCACUGAAUCAAAGGCACAAUAGCUAUCUUUUCACUUGAGCUCAGAAAAGUAAAAUGGCUUAAUUUGAACUAUUAAUUUUCAGUGGCCUCUAAUUAAACAAAAACAAAAAACCACAAAUACUGGCUAGGUAAGAUAUUCCUGAGGUCAUUUUAAAAGAAGUGUGGCACCUAGGAUUCAAUAUUUAAUGCUAACAGUAUUAUAUUUUAGUGAAAUUUAUUUUGGUGGUGACAGUUUAUUAAACCUAAUUAGACUUCUUUCAAUAGCUUGUUGUAGAGACAAUCUCAAGGGCUGGAAAGUGUUGCUAAAAUGAAUGUCAUACAUUUCUGAUAUACUAAGGAGCUUAUAAAGUAAUUCUUUCAUAGUGCAAGAAUUAUUAAUUUCUUAGAGGAUGUUUUUAAAGGAGCUACUUAAUUGGGAAAAUGUUCUUUAAAUAUCAGUAAUAGUUCAUUAAGUAACAUAGUAGCUAAGAACAUGGACUAUAUUUUCACAGCAUAGUUCAGCUUAGGCACACCUUUAGUUUGGAUUAUUGGCAUUCUCUUACGUAGGAAUUAUAUCAUUGUAGAUAUGUAAUUAUGGUAAUAAGCAAUUUUCAUAACCAUGCUCACUCAGACUAUAUCAUUUGAAACUGCCAUGUUUCCAUUUUUGACAAUUCAUGUUCACAAAACAACAGGAACAAUUUCCUAUUUGGUAUAAAGAGCAAAAUUUCCAACUUUGCCCCAAAAUGCCAUGGGUGGCAUAUUGCCAUAUGAUUAUAUCAUAUAUUUAAUCAUGUAUGGGAAAGAUUUUGGAUUUUUUUUCUUAUUUAAAAAAGUGCUAAAUAUAAGAAUAUAGUUUUAAAUCAGCAAGUCUAAUAACACUAUUGCAGCUGUACACAGAGAGAACCUUUUGUGCCUUUUUGCCUGCAGUAAGCAUUUAUUUCUAUUUUACAUGAGUUCUAAGAAUGUUGAUGAUUAUUGCACCUUGUUCUUCUGUAUAUAAACUUGAUUAAGGAAUUUUUUUUUUUAAAGCAAGGAGCCGUUUUUUGUUACUAGGUGGAUACCUUAGUAAACAUGAGGGGAAUUAUCAGAUAGAUGUCUUUGGAGCCCAGCCUUCCCUGUGUAGUGAGCUGGAAACUCCUUUAGAUUGUAUUCAUUGGUGUGUAUGUAUAUGUACAUAUAUGUAUAAAUAGUUAAAUACAUAAACAUAAAACUUAACAUCGCAUUGUUGUGAUGACAAGAAGUAGUAAGGUGCUAGGUGGUUACAUUAAAAAGCACAGCACAGUGUAUAAUCAGUCACUAUGACUGGUGGUUUUGUAAGCUGGGUUCAGUUUUUGAACCACCCAGAAUACCUCAUGUGUAAAUACAGUGUUCAUGACUUAAUUGAAAUACAGUUAUUGUUUAAAAAAAAAAAAAAAGAAUGUGAAGCCACUGGUUGGCUUAUGCCUUCUGAUCUAUCAUUCUUGCCUCUUUUUUUGUAAAGGGGUUUUCUUCUUGUUGUUCUGUUUUUUAAUAGGGUUUACAGCUAGAAUUUUGAAUGCCAAAGUUCUAUUUAUUAAAUUAAGAAAAAAGUUUUCAAUGUUAAUGGCUAGUAUUUUUCCACUGGACUAUUGUUUGUUGAUGUUGGAAUUUGUAUUUACAGAGAAAUAAAUUUUUUAUAAAAAGA